CGAAACCAUAGAGACGUCCGCGGGAACCAAAAUCACGGUUUUUCCAGGAGAAACCAUUGCGGAGCCCAAUUUGCCGCAGCUGGAAGUCCUGGAUAGUUCCCACCUGAAAGUCUGUUUGCAAAGGCAAUGCGCACUCAGGCACCAGAGGGCAGAGGGGCUCAAGUUCCAGGGUUUUAAGGUGCUUGGAACUCCCAGGAGCCUGGCAAACCUUCAUCCAGAACCUCUUCCUCAAGCAAGACAAAAAGCUGCUAAGCACUGCUCCCUCCGUCUCUGUGAAGAGACCAGCUUCUAACAGACGGUGCCGGGCUGACCCCCCAUCAUGCCAGGCUGGCUCACCCUCCCCACACUCUGCCGCUUCCUUCUUUGGGCCUUCACCAUCUUCCACAAAGCCCAAGGAGACCCAGCAUCCCACCCGGGCCCCCACUACCUCCUGCCCCCCAUCCACGAGGUCAUUCACUCUCAUCGUGGGGCCACGGCCACGCUGCCCUGCGUCCUGGGCACCACGCCUCCCAGCUACAAGGUGCGCUGGAGCAAGGUGGAGCCUGGGGAGCUCCGGGAAACGCUGAUCCUCAUCACCAACGGACUGCACGCCCGGGGGUAUGGGCCCCUGGGAGGGCGCGCCAGGAUGCGGAGGGGGCAUCGACUAGACGCCUCCCUGGUCAUCGCGGGCGUGCGCCUGGAGGACGAGGGCCGGUACCGCUGCGAGCUCAUCAACGGCAUCGAGGACGAGAGCGUGGCGCUGACCUUGAGCUUGGAGGGUGUGGUGUUUCCGUACCAACCCAGCCGGGGCCGGUACCAGUUCAAUUACUACGAGGCGAAGCAGGCGUGCGAGGAGCAGGACGGACGCCUGGCCACCUACUCCCAGCUCUACCAGGCUUGGACCGAGGGUCUGGACUGGUGUAACGCGGGCUGGCUGCUCGAGGGCUCCGUGCGCUACCCUGUGCUCACCGCACGCGCCCCGUGCGGCGGCCGAGGCCGGCCCGGGAUCCGCAGCUACGGACCCCGCGACCGGAUGCGCGACCGCUACGACGCCUUCUGCUUCACCUCCGCGCUGGCGGGCCAAGUGUUCUUCGUGCCCGGGCGGCUGACGCUGUCUGAAGCCCACGCGGCGUGCCGGCGACGCGGCGCCGUGGUGGCCAAGGUUGGGCACCUCUACGCCGCCUGGAAGUUUUCGGGGCUAGACCAGUGCGACGGCGGCUGGCUGGCUGACGGCAGUGUGCGCUUCCCAAUCACCACGCCGAGGCCGCGCUGCGGGGGGCUCCCGGAUCCCGGAGUGCGCAGUUUCGGCUUCCCCAGGCCCCAACAGGCAGCCUAUGGGACCUACUGCUACGCCGAGAAUUAGGCGCCCACCGUGUCCCCUCCAGCGCGCGCGAAGAAGCUUGGGAGUCGUGGCGGGGGUCUCUCGCCACCCCUUUCCGGAGAGCCUCCCCUCCCUCCAGACCCGGAGCGGCCUCUCCAGACCUGCCUUCCCAGCCGGGGGCUGCGGGCCUCGGACCCCGGCUGGCCCGGCGGCGGGGAGGGGAGGCGGGGGCGCCUCCGGCGGCGAGAUGCAGAGGUGACCCUCGGACCCGCUGCCGUUCGCGAACCCUAGCAGAGGACUCAGCCACCGCCGGGGGGAGGGUGAGGCGGCCGGGGGCAUUAACUGACCUCUGAGUACAGCAAUAAAAUAACCUGGGGAUCUUU